GCGCUCUCCCCGCCCCUCACCGCAGCCUGCAGCCGCGCUCACCUCCGCGGUCCGCCCCGGCGCCCCGGGACCCGUUAGUGCCCAGCCUGUGGGCCGACCGCGACCCCCGCCCGGCGCGAGCCUGCCCCCAGCUCUGCCGACACUUGACCCAGACCAGUCCCAACGCCCAGUGCGGCCGCCCGGGGAGCCGCGGGAGAGGCGGCGGCGGGGGGAGGAGGGAGAGGAGGGCCGAGCCGGCGGCACGGGAGGCCCGGUUUUGAAGCCGCUUCUCUGCCCGAGUUAGGUUUCGCCCAGCGCAAUUUCUUUCUCUAUGUACUUUGCGAAUAAGUUUCGGAGCAUCGGUUAACAGCCUAUGGGUGAAAUUUGGCUUUCAUUCAUGAAUGAGACGGUGUUUCGCCUUGUUGGCCAGGCUGGUCUGGAACUCCUGACCUCGUGAUCUGCCCACCUCUGCCUCCCAAAGUGCUGGGAUUACAAGUAAAUUAUUCUUGACAGAAGUAUUUUAAAAGAAAAAUCUUUACGAUGGCCUCAGCAGUACUUAGUUCUGUUCCCACCACCGCUUCUCGUUUUGCCCUGUUACAAGUGGAUAGUGGCAGUGGCUCUGAUUCUGAACCUGGAAAAGGUAAAGGUCGAAAUACUGGAAAGUCUCAAACUUUAGGAAGCAAGUCAACUACAAAUGAGAAAAAAAGAGAGAAAAGAAGAAAAAAGAAGGAACAGCAACAGAGUGAAGCAAAUGAGCUCAGGAAUCUUGCUUUUAAGAAAAUUCCCCAGAAAUCCUCCCAUGCUGUUUGUAACGCUCAACAUGAUCUUCCAUUGUCAAACCCAGUACAGAAGGAUUCACGAGAAGAAAAUUGGCAAGAGUGGAGACAAAGAGAUGAGCAGCUGACAUCUGAAAUGUUUGAAGCAGAUCUUGAGAAGGCAUUGUUACUAAGUAAACUAGAAUAUGAAGAGCACAAAAAGGAGUAUGAAGAUGCUGAAAAUACUUCAACUCAGUCCAAAGUUAUGAAUAAAAAAGAUAAAAGAAAGAAUCAUCAGGGAAAAGACAGACCUCUCACAGUAUCACUAAAAGAUUUUCAUUCGGAAGAUCACAUUAGUAAAAAGACUGAGGAAUUGAGUUCUUCUCAGACUUUAUCACAUGAUGGAGGAUUCUUCAAUAGACUGGAAGAUGAUGUUCAUAAAAUUCUUAUUAGAGAAAAACGAAGAGAACAGCUUACAGAAUAUAAUGGAACAGAUAAUUGUACAGCUCAUGAACACAACCAGGAAGUGGUUCUGAAAGAUGGAAGAAUUGAAAGACUAAAGUUAGAGCUUGAAAGGAAAGAUGCUGAAAUCCAGAAGCUGAAAAAUGUAAUCACUCAAUGGGAGGCAAAGUAUAAGGAAGUAAAGGCAAGAAAUGCACAAUUAUUGAAAAUGCUUCAGGAAGGUGAAAUGAAAGAUAAGGCAGAAAUACUUCUGCAAGUUGAUGAAUCACAAAGUAUCAAGAAUGAGCUCACUAUUCAGGUGACUUCACUUCAUGCUGCAUUAGAACAAGAAAGAUCUAAAGUGAAAGUAUUACAAGCAGAGUUAGCCAAAUACCAGGGUGGCAGAAAAGGGAAAAGAAACUCUGAAUCCGACCAGUGUAGGUGAUUACAUUAGCCUUUGAAGUCAACACAAAGUUUAAAACUUCCAGGAUUUUGCAAAGUUGUAUAUAUUUAAUGCUGUGCAACUGCUAAACUAUGCAGUUUUUCUUGAAGGAACUAAAAGCAACUAGCUCCCUAAUGGUCUAUAAUUUUAUUUCUUUUGGCUUAAAGUGAAAAAGAAGAAAUAGAGAAUUCCAGCAGAAUUCAGUGGUUGUCUACUAUCCAUACUUCUUAUCACUUUAGUUUUUCAUCAGUCAAUAAAAUUAAUUUACUCUUCCA